AGUCUCCGGCCGAGUCUUCUCGCAGCCGCAACCCACCUGGGGCCAGCCCAGAGCUGCCAGCGCCGCUCGGCUCCCUCCCUCCCUCCCGGCCCUUCGGCCGCGGCGGCGUGCGCCUGCCUUUUCCGGGGGCGGGGGCCUGGCCCGCGCGCUCCCCUCCCGCAGGCGCCACCUCGGACAUCCCCGGGAUUGCUACUUCUCUGCCAACUUCGCCAACUCGCCAGCACUUGGAGAGGCCCGGCUCCCCUCCCGGCGCCCUCUGACCGCCCCCGCCCCGCGCGCUCUCCGACCACCGCCUCUCGGAUGACCAGGUUCCAGGGGAGCUGAGCGAGUCGCCUCCCCCGCCCAGCUUCAGCCCUGGCUGCAGCUGCAGCGCGAGCCAUGCGCCCCCAGUGCACCCCGGCCCGGCCCACCGCCCCGGGGCCAUUCUGCUGACCGCCCAGCCCCGAGCCCCGACAGUGGCAAGUUGCGGCUACUGCAGUUGCAAGCUCCGGCCAACCCGGAGGAGCCCCAGCGGGGAGCGCAGUGCUGCGCCCCCCGCCCCCGCGCGCCCCGCAGCAGCCGGGCGUUCACUCAUCCUCCCUCCCCCACCGUCCCUCCCUUUUCUCCUCAAGUCCUGAAGUUGAGUUUGAGAGGCGACACGGCGGCGGCGGCCGCGCUGCUCCCGCUCCUCUGCCUCCCCAUGGAUAUGCACUGCAAAGCAGACCCCUUCUCCGCGAUGCACCCAGGGCACGGGGGUGUGAACCAGCUCGGGGGGGUGUUUGUGAACGGCCGGCCCCUACCCGACGUGGUGAGGCAGCGCAUCGUGGAGCUGGCCCACCAGGGUGUGCGGCCCUGUGACAUCUCCCGGCAGCUGCGGGUCAGCCACGGCUGUGUCAGCAAAAUCCUGGGCAGGUACUACGAGACCGGCAGCAUCAAGCCGGGUGUGAUCGGUGGCUCCAAGCCCAAAGUGGCGACGCCCAAAGUGGUGGACAAGAUUGCUGAAUACAAACGACAGAACCCGACUAUGUUCGCCUGGGAGAUUCGAGACCGGCUCCUGGCCGAGGGCAUCUGUGACAAUGACACAGUGCCCAGCGUCUCUUCCAUCAACAGAAUCAUCCGGACCAAAGUUCAGCAGCCUUUCCACCCAACGCCGGAUGGGGCUGGGACAGGAGUGACCGCCCCUGGCCACACCAUUGUUCCCAGCACGGCCUCCCCUCCUGUUUCCAGCGCCUCCAAUGACCCAGUGGGAUCCUACUCCAUCAAUGGGAUCCUGGGGAUUCCUCGCUCCAAUGGUGAGAAGAGGAAACGUGAUGAAGAUGUGUCUGAGGGCUCAGUCCCCAAUGGAGAUUCCCAGAGUGGUGUGGACAGUUUGCGGAAGCACUUGCGAGCUGACACCUUCACCCAGCAGCAGCUGGAAGCUUUGGAUCGGGUCUUUGAGCGUCCUUCCUACCCUGACGUCUUCCAGGCAUCAGAGCACAUCAAAUCAGAACAGGGGAACGAGUACUCCCUCCCAGCCCUGACCCCUGGGCUUGAUGAAGUCAAGUCGAGUCUAUCUGCAUCCACCAACCCUGAGCUGGGCAGCAACGUGUCAGGCACACAGACAUACCCAGUUGUGACUGGUCGUGACAUGGCGAGCACCACUCUGCCUGGUUACCCCCCUCACGUGCCCCCCACUGGCCAGGGAAGCUACCCCACCUCCACCCUGGCAGGAAUGGUGCCUGAGGCUGCAGUUGGUCCCUCAUCCUCCCUCAUGAGCAAGCCGGGGAGGAAGCUUGCAGAAGUGCCCCCUUGUGUGCAACCCACUGGAGCGAGUUCUCCGGCAACCCGUACAGCCACCCCCAGUACACGGCCUACAACGAGGCUUGGAGAUUCAGCAACCCCGCCUUACUAAGUUCCCCUUAUUAUUAUAGUGCCGCCCCCCGGGGCUCCGCCCCUGCCGCUGCUGCCGCUGCCUAUGACCGCCACUAGUUACCGCGGGGACCACAUCAAGCUUCAGGCCGACAGCUUCGGCCUCCACAUCGUCCCCGUCUGACCCCACCCCGGAGGGAGGGAGGACCGACGCGACGCGAUGCCUCCCGGCCACCGCCCCAGCCUCACCCCAUCCCACGACCCCCGCAACCCUUCACAUCACCCCCCUCGAAGGUCGGACAGGACGGGUGGAGCCGUGGGCGGGACCCUCAGGCCCGGGCCCGCCGCCCCCAGCCCCGCCUGCCGCCCCUCCCCGCCUGCCUGGACUGCGCGGCGCCGUGAGGGGGAUUCGGCCCAGCUCGUCCCGGCCUCCACCAAGCCAGCCCCGAAGCCCGCCAGCCACCCUGCCGGACUCGGGCGCGACCUGCUGGCGCGCGCCGGAUGUUUCUGUGACACACAAUCAGCGCGGACCGCAGCGCGGCCCAGCCCCGGGCACCCGCCUCGGACGCUCGGGCGCCAGGAGGCUUCGCUGGAGGGGCUGGGCCAAGGAGAUUAAGAAGAAAACGACUUUCUGCAGGAGGAAGAGCCCGCUGCCGAAUCCCUGGGAAAAAUUCUUUUCCCCCAGUGCCAGCCGGACUGCCCUCGCCUUCCGGGUGUGCCCUGUCCCAGAAGAUGGAAUGGGGGUGUGGGGGUCCGGCUCUAGGAACGGGCUUUGGGGGCGUCAGGUCUUUCCAAGGUUGGGACCCAAGGAUCGGGGGGCCCAGCAGCCCGCACCGAUCGAGCCGGACUCUCGGCUCUUCACUGCUCCUCCUGGCCUGCCUAGUUCCCCAGGGCCCGGCACCUCCUGCUGCGAGACCCGGCUCUCAGCCCUGCCUUGCCCCUACCUCAGCGUCUCUUCCACCUGCUGGCCUCCCAGUUUCCCCUCCUGCCAGUCCUUCGCCUGUCCCUUGACGCCCUGCAUCCUCCUCCCUGACUCGCAGCCCCAUCGGACGCUCUCCCGGGACCGCCGCAGGACCAGUUUCCAUAGACUGCGGACUGGGGUCUUCCUCCAGCAGUUACUUGAUGCCCCCUCCCCCGACACAGACUCUCAAUCUGCCGGUGGUAAGAACCGGUUCUGAGCUGGCGUCUGAGCUGCUGCGGGGUGGAAGUGGGGGGCUGCCCACUCCACUCCUCCCAUCCCCUCCCAGCCUCCUCCUCCGGCAGGAACUGAACAGAACCACAAAAAGUCUACAUUUAUUUAAUAUGAUGGUCUUUGCAAAAAGGAACAAAACAACACAAAAGCCCACCAGGCUGCUGCUUUGUGGAAAGACGGUGUGUGUCGUGUGAAGGCGAAACCCGGUGUACAUAACCCCUCCCCCUCCGCCCCGCCCCGCCCGGCCCCGUAGAGUCCCUGUCGCCCGCCGGCCCUGCCUGUAGAUACGCCCCGCUGUCUGUGCUGUGAGAGUCGCCGCUCGCUGGGGGGGAAGGGGGGGACACAGCUACACGCCCAUUAAAGCACAGCACGUCCUGGGGGAGGGGGGCAUUUUUUAUGUUACAAAAAAAAAUUACGAAAGAAAAGAAAUCUCUAUGCAAAAUGACGAACAUGGUCCUGUGGACUCCUCUGGCCUGUUUUGUUGGCUCUUUCUCUGUAAUUCCGUGUUUUCGCUUUUUCCUCCCUGCCCCUCUCUCCCUCUGCCCCUCUCUCCUCUCCGCUUCUCUCCCCCUCUGUCUCUGUCUCUCUCCGUCUCUGUCGCUCUUGUCUGUCUGUCUCUGCUCUUUCCUCGGCCUCUCUCCCCAGACCUGGCCCGGCCGCCCUGUCUCCGCAGGCUAGAUCCGAGGUGGCAGCUCCAGCCCCCGGGCUCGCCCCCUCGCGGGCGUGCCCCGCGCGCCCCGGGCGGCCGAAGGCCGGGCCGCCCCGUCCCGCCCCGUAGUUGCUCUUUCGGUAGUGGCGAUGCGCCCUGCAUGUCUCCUCACCCGUGGAUCGUGACGACUCGAAAUAACAGAAACAAAGUCAAUAAAGUGAAAAUAAAUAAAAAUCCUUGAACAAAUCCGAAAAGGCUUGGAGUCCUCGCCCAGAUCUCUCUCCCCUGCGAGCCCUUUUUAUUUGAGAAGGAAAAAGAGAAAAGAGAAUCGUUUAAGGGAACCCGGCGCCCAGCCAGGCUCCAGUGGCCCGAACGGGGCGGCGAGGGCGGCGAGGGCGCCGAGGUCCGGCCCAUCCCAGUCCUGUGGGGCUGGCCGGGCAGAGACCCCGGACCCAGGCCCAGGCCUAACCUGCUAAAUGUCCCCGGACGGUUCUGGUCUCCUCGGCCACUUUCAGUGCGUCGGUUCGUUUUGAUUCUUUUUCUUUUGUGCACAUAAGAAAUAAAUAAUAAUAAUAAAUAAAGAAUAAAAUUUUGUAUGUCACUC